CUCUUCGUUAAGUCGGCCUUCCCAACAUGGCGCAGUCUAUUAACAUCACGGAGCUGAAUCUGCCGCAGCUAGAAAUGCUCAAGAACCAGCUGGACCAGGAAGUGGAGUUCUUGUCCACGUCCAUUGCUCAGCUCAAAGUGGUACAGACCAAGUAUGUGGAAGCCAAGGACUGUCUGAACGUGCUGAACAAGAGCAACGAGGGGAAAGAAUUACUCGUCCCACUGACGAGUUCUAUGUAUGUCCCUGGGAAGCUGCAUGAUGUGGAACACGUGCUCAUCGAUGUGGGAACUGGGUACUAUGUAGAGAAGACAGCUGAGGAUGCCAAGGACUUCUUCAAGAGGAAGAUAGAUUUUCUAACCAAGCAGAUGGAGAAAAUCCAACCAGCUCUUCAGGAGAAGCACGCCAUGAAACAGGCCGUCAUGGAAAUGAUGAGUCAGAAGAUUCAGCAGCUCACAGCCCUGGGGGCAGCUCAGGCUACUGCUAAGGCCUGAGAGUUUUUGCAGAAAUGGGGCAGAGGGACACCCUUUGGGCGUGGCUUCCUGGUGAUGGGAAGGGUCUUGUGUUUUAAUGCCAAUAAAUGUGCCAGCUGGGCAGAA